AGACCGGCCGACGCGGGCCACCCCGCUCUCCUCGCCGCCGCGGCGGCAGGCGCGGGGCCGCGCCGCGAGGCCUGAUCCCUGCAGCGCGGGCAGGCGGCGUCGCAGAGCGGAGCUAGCUGGAUGCGUCCGGACUCCUGCAGGUGAGAGUGAUUUUCCAGUGAUUGCUUUGGCCUGUACAACCAGAGAACAGGAUUCUUCCCUUCUUUUUGGCCACCAAAUGCCUAUGUGCACCACACAUUCCAGUGUGCUGAGAAGGGCAGAGCUUCUUGGAUGAUGAUGGACGUCCCACCGGGCAGGAUGAAGGCAGAGCGUGUGGCAUCUCCACCUCAAGGUUCUGCAGGCUGUACAGGAGGCAUGGCUGGGGAGGCCUCAGGAAAUUUACAGUCCUGGCAGCAGGUGAAAGGGAAGCCAGCAUGUCUUACAUGGCAGAGCAGGAGAGAGAGAGAGUGAAGGGGGAGAUGCUACACGCUUUGAAAGAGCCAGAUCUCAUGAGAACUCUGUCACGAGACAGUGCUUGGGGGAUGAUGCUAAGCCAUUAGAAACCACCCCCAUGAUCCAAUCACCUCCCACCAGGCUCCACCUGCAACACGCAGGAUCACAAUUCAACAUGAGAUUUAGGUGGGGACACAGAGCCAAACCAUAUUAGGUGGACUCCACUUGAACCUUUGAGCUGCAUAUAACCUCUGCUAUGAAGCUUCUCCAGGUGCAGCCUGAUCUUCCUCUUCUCCCUUGCCAGCCAGCACUCUGCCUUCUGUAUCCACCAUGGUGUUUGGUGAGUUUUUCCAUCGCCCUGGACAAGACGAGGAACUUGUCAACCUGAAUGUGGGGGGCUUUAAGCAGUCUGUUGACCAAAGCACCCUCCUGCGGUUUCCUCACACCAGACUGGGGAAGCUGCUUACUUGCCAUUCUGAAGAGGCCAUUCUGGAGCUGUGUGAUGAUUACAGUGUGGCCGAUAAGGAGUACUACUUUGAUCGGAAUCCCUCCUUGUUCAGAUAUGUUUUGAAUUUUUAUUACACGGGGAAGCUGCAUGUCAUGGAGGAGCUGUGCGUAUUCUCAUUCUGCCAGGAGAUCGAGUACUGGGGCAUCAACGAGCUCUUCAUUGAUUCUUGCUGCAGCAAUCGCUACCAGGAACGCAAGGAGGAAAACCACGAGAAGGACUGGGACCAGAAAAGCCAUGAUGUGAGUACCGACUCCUCGUUUGAAGAGUCGUCUCUGUUUGAGAAAGAGCUGGAGAAGUUUGACACACUGCGAUUUGGUCAGCUCCGGAAGAAAAUCUGGAUUAGAAUGGAGAAUCCAGCGUACUGCCUGUCCGCUAAGCUUAUCGCUAUCUCCUCCUUGAGCGUGGUGCUGGCCUCCAUCGUGGCCAUGUGCGUUCACAGCAUGUCGGAGUUCCAGAAUGAGGAUGGAGAAGUGGAUGAUCCGGUGCUGGAAGGAGUGGAGAUCGCGUGCAUUGCCUGGUUCACCGGGGAGCUUGCCGUCCGGCUGGCUGCCGCUCCUUGUCAAAAGAAAUUCUGGAAAAACCCUCUGAACAUCAUUGACUUUGUCUCUAUUAUUCCCUUCUAUGCCACGUUGGCUGUAGACACCAAGGAGGAAGAGAGUGAGGAUAUUGAGAACAUGGGCAAGGUGGUCCAGAUCCUACGGCUUAUGAGGAUUUUCCGAAUUCUAAAGCUUGCCCGGCACUCGGUAGGACUUCGGUCUCUAGGUGCCACACUGAGACACAGCUACCAUGAAGUUGGGCUUCUGCUUCUCUUCCUCUCUGUGGGCAUUUCCAUUUUCUCUGUGCUUAUCUACUCCGUGGAGAAAGAUGACCACACAUCCAGCCUCACCAGCAUCCCCAUCUGCUGGUGGUGGGCCACCAUCAGCAUGACAACUGUGGGCUAUGGAGACACCCACCCGGUCACCUUGGCGGGAAAGCUCAUCGCCAGCACAUGCAUCAUCUGUGGCAUCUUGGUGGUGGCCCUUCCCAUCACCAUCAUCUUCAACAAGUUUUCCAAGUACUACCAGAAGCAAAAGGACAUUGAUGUGGACCAGUGCAGUGAGGAUGCACCAGAGAAGUGUCAUGAGCUACCUUACUUUAACAUUAGGGAUAUAUAUGCACAGCGGAUGCACACCUUCAUUACCAGUCUCUCUUCUGUAGGCAUUGUGGUGAGCGAUCCUGACUCCACAGAUGCUUCAAGCAUUGAAGACAAUGAGGACAUUUGUAACACCACCUCCUUGGAGAAUUGCACAGCAAAAUGAGCGGGGGUGUUUGUGCCUGUUUCUCUUAUCCUUUCCCGACAUUAGGUUAACACAGCUUUAUAAACCUCAGUGGGUUCGUUAAAAUCAUUUAAUUCUCAGGGUGUACCUUUCAGCCAUAGUUGGACAUUCAUUGCUGAAUUCUGAAAUGAUAGAAUUGUCUUUAUUUUUCUCUGUGAGGUCAAUUAAAUGCCUUGUUCUGAAAUUUAUUUUUUACAAGAGAGAGUUGUGAUAUAGUUUGGAAUAUAAGAUAAAUGGUAUUGGGUGGGGUUUGUGGCUACAGCUUAUGCAUCAUUCUGUGUUUGUCAUUUACUCACAUUGAGCUAACUUUAAAUUACUGACAAGUAGAAUCAAAGGUGCAGCUGACUGAGACGACAUGCAUGUAAGAUCCACAAAAUGAGACAAUGCAUGUAAAUCCAUGCUCAUGUUCUAAACAUGGAAACUAGGAGCCUAAUAAACUUCCUAAUUCAGUAUGGA